AAUCCGGAAACGGCGGCGGCGGCGACAGGACCGAGGGGCCUUAGUUGGUGGGCAAGUCGGGGAUCCCAGAAAGAGAAGCGUGACCCGGAAGCGGAAACGGGUGUCCGUCCCAGCUCCGGUGAGUGGCCCCUGCUGGACCGUGGAUCCCGGGCGGGCGUGCGGGCGGCAGCGUACGAGGCCUUCUACUCGCCCGGGUGUCCGGUGCCUCGCUUCUCCCUGGGACCCUGUCGUCAACAUCGAGGCCUGCCAGUGAGCUUCUACCAUCAUGGACCUAUUGUUCGGGCGCCGGAAGACGCCAGAGGAGCUACUGCGGCAGAACCAGAGGGCCCUGAACCGUGCCAUGCGGGAGCUGGACCGCGAGCGACAGAAACUAGAGACCCAGGAGAAGAAAAUCAUUGCAGACAUUAAGAAGAUGGCCAAGCAAGGCCAGAUGGAUGCUGUUCGCAUCAUGGCAAAAGACUUGGUGCGCACCCGGCGCUAUGUGCGCAAGUUUGUAUUGAUGCGGGCCAACAUCCAGGCUGUGUCCCUCAAGAUCCAGACACUCAAGUCCAACAACUCGAUGGCACAAGCCAUGAAGGGUGUCACCAAGGCCAUGGGCACCAUGAACAGACAGCUGAAGUUGCCCCAGAUCCAGAAGAUCAUGAUGGAGUUUGAGCGGCAGGCAGAGAUCAUGGAUAUGAAGGAGGAGAUGAUGAAUGAUGCCAUUGAUGAUGCCAUGGGUGAUGAGGAAGAUGAAGAGGAGAGUGAUGCUGUGGUGUCCCAGGUUCUGGAUGAGCUGGGACUUAGCCUAACAGAUGAGCUGUCGAGUGAGUGCUCCAAAUCCUGGACCCCAUUUCCCACCCAAGGCCCAGCCACAGCUCCAAGCCCUCCCUUUCCCUGCAUUACUCCCCUCCGCUGCCUGACCCCACCUGCUCAAACCCCCACUUUCUCUGCAGACCUCCCCUCAACUGGGGGCUCGCUUAGUGUGGCUGCUGGUGGGAAAAAAGCAGAGGCCGCAGCCUCAGCCCUAGCUGAUGCUGAUGCAGACCUGGAGGAACGGCUUAAGAACCUGCGGAGGGACUGAGUGCCCCUGCCACUCCGAGAUAACCAGUGGAUGCCCAGGAUCUUUUACCACAACCCCUCUGUAAUAAAAGAGAUUUGACACUA